CCGGCCUCAGCCGGCGCACCUGGCGGAGGAGGAACCUCGCGACGCGCUCUCGGGCAUCGGUUUCUCCCAGCAAAGCUUGGAGGGUUUAGCUGCGCGGAGAGCUCAGCGAGCUCUUCUGUGUCUGUUUGGGGCGUGUGGGCUCCGGGAGCGUGAGGACCGGGAAGCUAGGAGGCUCCUUCCCUUCUGGCGGCUCCCUCACUGAGACCGGGCGGUUUGGUUGCGGGGGAAGUGGAGACGAGCCACCCUUGACCUUUGACUGCAAGAACUCACCUUGAGCAGGAUAGAGGCACGUGGACGGUGACCCUCGGGAUGCAAUAAAUGCUGAGACAGAUCAGGUGUGCAAGGCACAGAGCUAGAGGCCAGAGGCCUUUCUUCUCCAACCUUCAGUCACCUCUUUUUAAAGUGAAGCCAGCAUCCUCCUCGGGGUUUACUGUGAAAAUUAAGUGAGCUGACGCGUGCUGUGUUUUGAUGUUGCUUGGCUCCUACAAACAUUGAGUGGGCCAGACACUGUUCUGAAAAAUACGCAGUCGACUUUUGAACAGCACAGGCUUGAACUGCAUGCGGCCACUAAUACUCGGACUUCCUUCUGCCUCUGCCAUCCCUAAGACAGCAAGACCCACCCCUCCUGCUCCUCAGCCUACUCGAUGUGAUGAUGGAGCAACGUUCCUGCUACCACUUUCCUUGAACCUCACUUUUCUUGGAAGACUUCCCUGACUGCUCCCAGGUUGGGUCAGGGGCCCAUCUGAGAUCCCGAAGCACUGAGCACAUUGUGAUGUCACUGUCUUCAUCACCCGGACUCCCUUGGAGCCAGGCACUGGCUUAAUCCUAUCUCCAUUUCCCCUGUGCCCAGCACAUAGUUAGUGCUCCAGAUGAUGGGAGACUCAAUGGAGAGACACGUGAGUGGAUGGAUGUUUUGCUGAAGGCAUCCAAUGUGGCAGAACCGGCAGCAGCAAACUGAUUCUGUCUGGAAUUUGGAAGCCAGGGAGGAACAGCCUCGAAUGGACAGGAUGCAGAGAUUCAGAGAGUCUAAGCAACUUUUCUAAAUCAUCUAGCUGGAAUUCAGUAACUGAGCCAGGAUCUACCCCAGGUCUGUCUGACUCCAAAGCCUGUGUCUUCCAGCACACACUGCUGCUGCCUGGGCAGGAAUGUGGAUAUGAUGUCUGGAGCUCUAGCAACCAUAUCAGACCACAAGGAUGAAUGUACACCCCAGGAAUGGAAGAGAGGAAAGCCAGAAAAAGACUCGGUCCCUGAUGGCUGAAGAGCUACCAUACCUGCCCCUAGAUCUUCUAUUUCUGAUCAUCUUCUAUGCAAGGGGAAUGAUGGUGGUCAAAGAAGCCAGGUAACCCACAGAUCCCAGUACCCACAGAUCCCGGAAACAGCCCCUCCAAACCACGGAGCGGAGUGAAGGAGGCAGUGUCCAGAUCGCAGAGGGCUUUCAUGCCCACUUUCUCCCAACGGCCUUACAAAUGACCCUGGCAAGGCAUGCAUUCACCCAGGUCAGAGCUCAAUAAAUACUUGUGGUGUGAGUAAAUGAGCCCCAGGUUAUAACUGGGGAAAUUGAGGCCAGGAGAAACCAGGUAAAGUCAUAAAGAAGAGCCAGAACCCCACGACCAGUCAUCUGAUGCUCCCUCCACCCCAUCACCCCUCAAGGGCCUCUGCAGGCAGCAGUUUAAUCUGAAGCAAAUCCUAAAAUAGUCCUCAAGAAGAUGAGCACAUCCCAGCUCUAAUUCGCCCUCCAAGUGCCUCGAAAGAUCUUUUCUAACAAAAACACAGAAAUGAUUUUUACAAUCCAACCAACCAUCAGCUCCAUGAACCUUGAGAGAGACGGGAAGGCAGCCGCAACCUCUGCGAACUGAAAUGUAUUGUCAGAAGGAUGUAAUUACAAGUAUUUAUGUACACUGAUUCUGAACCAGAGAAUCCCGGGAUGGCUCUGGGGCCAAAAAAAAAAAAAAAAAAAAAGAGAGAGAAAGAGGGAGAGAGAAAAAAAAGGCUUAAAAACUCCUGACAAUGAGCAAUUCUUCAUGGAACAAAACUAUUACAAUAGCCAGCCUUUGAUCUUGCCCGUCUCCUGUUGCCAAUUGUAUUUUGUCACCAUUGGACUGUCACCCGCGAGGGAGCACUUUUGAAUUAAGCAGUCUACAGCAAUUUAGUCUGCACUGGCUUUGAAGUGCCAACAUCAGUCAGGCCAGGACUAACUUUUUUCAUUAAAAAUUUUUCAGCUUCUCUAAGGGAGCUUUUUGCCUUUUUUUUUUUUUUUUUUAAGCCUGCCGGGACAUUUAGAUAAGUUGAGCCUCCAACCCGUGGCCCCAAGACAUCAAAAGGCGCGGGGUCCAGUAAUGCUGGAGGCAGCCAUCACUAAGCCCUAAUGGAGUGCUUCAUUAAGAUCGCUUCAAAGGCCCCCGUUUACAGACUCGGAGAUUGACUAAUUUACACAUUGUGGGAAAAUUGCUACCAGCUCUGCCCACACCCCAGCAGGGGGAGAGACGCCCUCUUUCUUUGAAAGGCAAGAACUGCAAAAGGCCCCUCUAAUUGCAGACUGGCCUUUACAAGGGAAAAACCCAGGCCCUGCCCUAAAUUUUGCAUUCGGCUGCCUUAGCACUCUGCGUCCUCGCACCGACCCUGGGGUCCUGUUUGUCCGGAGACAGCGUGGCACCAACCCAGCUGUGUGUGCUUUGGAGCUGGAUACUCCUAAACACGUUUGGGUUUGAACUCCAGCUCUGAUCCUGCCAGCGAGGAGCCUUAGAGCAAGUGACUUAACCUUCUGGGCCUCAGUUUCCCUCAUCUGAAAAUGGGCGUGAUCAAGUCACCUCCCAGGGAUAUUUUCGAGGAUGAGAGGUAAGGACGGCAGGAGAAGCUCAAUGUGCUGGCUACUUUUACCUUAGCGUAAACAUAUAAGAGAGCGAAAAGGCAUCCCUGAAACUGAAGCCAUGUUUUCACAAGCUGUCUUCACGGCUUAUUGAUUAUUUGAGAUGUUUGCACACAGACUGGGGCAUGAGGUCCAUAGAUAGGUGCGGGUCAGGCCCGUGGCUGUUUUGAGAACUGUGUUAUGUGGCCUCAAUGGCAGCACGUAACAGCAUCAAUUCAUCUAUUAAUAGUUUUCCUUUGUCGUAAAAGCAAGUUGGGAAGGGCGUGAUGAGGCGAGCUCUCUGGGAUGCUGUCAUGUGGAUUCACCCACGGGUCUGAAACCAGGGCUGGCUAUGGAAGGUUGGUCACCAGAGGCCCUGUGGGAAAAGCACCAAGCUCAGGGUGCAGUCACCCUUCCAGUCUGGCUCUGUCCCCAACGUCCUGAGCAACACCAACCAUGCCGCCUGUCCUCUCUGGUCAGCAGGGUUCUCCUGGGACUGAAAGGGCAAGGCCUAGGUAUGCCCAAAGCCUCCUCCCCAGCCUGAUGACUCGGGGUCUUCACCCCGCUUGAGGCCUCAGCAUCUCUGGGACCUUGUGAGAGAUGCAUGUUCAUAGGCUGCCCGGCCCUCCUGAAUGGGAAUCUGCAUUUGGAAUGAUCCCUGGUGAUUCGGGCACACAGUAAAGUGGAGGAGCUCUGCCCCAAUGCUUCUUUGGCCCAGGAAAACACAGUGAUGCUUGUUUCCUCAGGGGAUCCAGCCCGGUGACUUUGGCCUGGGAAGUCAUGAUUUUUGGGACUAACAGCCUGGCAGGCCCCUUGCCUACCACCCAACUGGGACUCAUUGUGUUUACAUCAGUGUCAUGCAGCUUUACUCUCUAGGGUCAUGUGGGGUCCCAAGUGAGGUAAAGGAAACUGCUGCGUCAUUCAUCGAGCACCUACUGUGUUCAGGCAUCCUGCUGGGUGCAGCGCACCUGGUAAGUAACUGAGAUUGUGAGUCAUUUGGUCUUUUGGUUGAGUCAUUGAGGAAGAGAUUGAGUGACUGGCCCAGGGUCACACAGUCAGUGAGUGGCCUCCUUCCAAGCACCCCCUGCACCACCCCCUGCACCAGGCUGCACAGAGGAAUCCCAGGGUGCCCAUUUCUGGAGGUGCCCCCCCGAAGAGGCUGGUUAGAUGGGGACCCAAGGGGAGGCCUGAACUGCCACGUCCUCCGGUAUUGUCCCCUUCCCCUCUACUUUCUAUUUGCCCAUCUUCCUAAUUAGAGGGAAAAAAUCUACACUCACUUCCUCUAUUCAACCUUUCACUUAAAAAAAAAAAAUGCAACUCCCACCCCCCUGGUUCCCAGCCUCGAAGGGAAGCCACCCUGGCCAGGGGCAAGCAUCGCAGCAAACCACUUAGCAAACCGCAAAUUUCAGAGGCCUCGUCACAUCUGCAUUUUAUCAGCUUUUUCCGGAUAGUAUUACCCCGAGCAAUUGUCUGCAGAUCGGCCGACAGCUGAGACGUUCAAGCUCUGAAUUACGGAGAAAGGGCCGGAGAUAAAGCCGAGCACAUGUAUCCCAUCAAAGUAAUGAAAGCCGCCUGCCGCCAGGACGCCCUGCUGCCUCCUUCCUAGCCGCCCUGCCGCCCCGCAGGAAGGCUGAUUAACCCUUGCGAGGCAGGGGAAGAAGAGCAGCGGUCAUCCAAUACUCAGGCUAAUCAGGGUCCCAAGAAUGGGAGGGAGGCAGAGGGGGUGGGCCGGAAAGAACAGCCAUCGCAGAGGGCCACUCUGACCUCAGGAUUAGACCUGCUGCAUUUCCUGUCACAGGACUUUGGUGGGACGGCAAAAAGGUAGAUGAAUAAAGGACUUGGUGUCCACAAGGUCCCAGAGACACUGCCUGGGUAUUAAGCAUUCCUAGAGGAGUGAGGGCAAGCAGUUUCCUGUGAGUAAGCCUUGCCUUGCUGUGAACGGAUGCCAUGUUUGCAAGAGUUGGUAAUAAUGUUUGCUGAGCACUUACUGUGGACUGGGCACCUUUGUUCCCCUUGCUUCCUGUCCCACCCCAUGGUGUGCUAUGCCUGGAGCUCACUGCAUUGAACUCCAGUGUCUCCUAGUGAGCGGUGGAUGCCAGGAUGUCCCCAGUCCUCUGCUCCCAUGACCAAUGCUACUUGGGUAUCCAUGUUCUGCUCUUCUAGGGGCCUAUGUGACAACUUCCCUGGCAUCCAUACCUCCACAGCCCAGAGUGGGGUCUCCGGGAUGUGAGCUGUACCCAGGCCUAACUUACGUCCGGACUGACCAGCACGCCUUCAGAAAGACUCUCAGGUUUACAGUACACGAGAGUGCACAGCUCUCCAAGACAUUCCAAGCAAUGUUACUUCAUCGACUUAUGGAAAUUUGCCUUUCUCAUAGUAAGUCUAAAGCAACGCUGCUGCUUUAAAAACUACCAGUCCUUUUUGCUGAGGAGUUCGAACAUCUCGUUAUCCUUGUUAACCGUUUAGACCUCUCUUCUGCCUUUCACAACCUGUGGCUAUUUUUCUAUCAGAUCUUUGAUGUUUUUCUUAUUGUUUGGUAAGAGUUCCGUGUAUAUUCCAAGUAGUCGCCACUCACCAGUUUGACUCUUUGCAGCAGCAUCCCGUGAGUCCUCUGUCUGCUGCCGUGGCCGGCGGUGCCCUGGGUGGACGGGAAUCCUUAGUUUUCACGCAGUCCAAUUCUUCAUAUUUGUCUCCUUCUGUCUUGUGCUCUUAGGGUCUUUUGGAGUAGAGUCAUUCCUUUUUAGGCACAAAGAUAUCUCCUUAUGCUUUUUUGAUUGGCUUUAUUAUUUUAGCAUUCACAUUUAGGCCCGUAAUCCAUCUGGAGCGCACCUUUUUUUUUUUUUUUUUUUUUUUUGAGACGGAGUCUCGCUCUGUCGCCCAGGCUGGAGUGCAGUGGCGGGAUCUCGGCUCACUGCAAUCUCCGCCUCCCGGGUUCACGCCAUUCUCCUGCCUCAGCCUCCCGAGUAGCUGGGACUACAGGCGCCCGCCACUACGCCCGGCUAAUUUUUUGUAUUUUUAGUAGAGACGGGGUUUCACCGUGUUAGCCGGGAUGGUCUCGAUCUCCUGACCUCGUGAUCCGCCCGCCUCGGCCUCCCAAAGUGCUGGGAUUACGGGCGUGAGCCACCGCGCCCGGCCGGAGCCCACCUUUUGAAAGGCUUAAGGAAGAGAUUAUCCAUUUUUAUUGAAGUAAGACAGCUCUGUCUGAUGCAGCAUGCUGUUGGCUUAACUGGACCUUUGAUUUCCCAGCAGGGACCUCAGCUUGCUCUGGGGCCUUGUCCUGCACCCCAGGUUCCCCAUCAAUGUCUUGGGGUGGGGAGCAUCACUUAAAGUCUCAUUUCCCUGCCACCUUCUCCACUUCCAUAAGCUGCUGCAUAGGUUUGGACAUCUUCUCUCUGUUUUGUAUUCAACCACAAUACACACAAACUAAAGGAGGCCAAGAUGAUAGAAGAUGGUUCUGCAGUUAGGACCCCUCCCACCCACCUUCAACCCAGCAUUGCAGCCUCGUGUGCAUCCUUGCCAGGGAUCUUUGCCAUUGCAGAUCCCUCUGCUGUGAGGGCUUUUCUUUCUUCAGUCCUUCCCAUCUGAUUGGCCAUCUCUCCCCUCAAGAGUCAGCUCAUUUGUUCACCAAUCUGUGUGAUCUGUGCACUAAAGAAUAAUGGAUAUGCUGUAUCUGCCAGAGUUUUCUGGGGAAAAGCAACACAGAUGGACGCCAGCAAACCUCAUGCAACAAAAGGCGCUAUUUCCAAGAUUUGGAGUAGCUCACAAAAGUCAAGAGAAGUUGAACCAUCAGGCUGCAGGAAGACAGGAAUUGGGUAGCUCUGGGUUUCUACAGAGCAGGAAGUAAGGGGAGAUCAGAAAACCUUGGUGUCAACUCUUAUCCCGCCUGGUGUCGCUCUCUCAUGCCUGAAGUUCUCAGCAGGGAGCACAGAAUUCGUUCAGCUUGGGUCAUGUGCUCAAAAAGGGUCAGACACCAUGACUGACCCUCCACCAAGACCGCUUGCAACAGGAAGGAGCUGGCUCCUGGAGGAAAACAACUCGCAAGGCUUCUGGCAGCCCAGACACGGGUCAUCCCUGAUGGGCUCUUUAUCCCAGCUGUGGCCUUGAUGAGUGCCGGACCCCUACGUGGGUCCCACAGUGCCUGCUCAAGGACCUCACAGCCCAGUGGAGGAGGCUAGUUAAGUAGAAAGUGCUCGAAACAAGGUAAAGAGUGCUGUGACAGAGGGGGCACAUGGGUAGGACCCCCUAACUCCAGGCGGAGCAUCAGAGAAGGCUUCCUGUAGGAAGCAGUGCUGUGCUGGGCAUACACAGAGCUGCAGGAGCUGGUUGAAUAGAGAAGCGGGGGAGGGUGUUCUGAGCAGAGGGUGAGCAAAACACGCAGUGAGAAAUAGACAAGCAGUUGAUGUGGGAAUGCAUUUCCUCCUGAGUAACAGAGGGGUCCUGGAAUGUUCCAUGUGGCCUCAGGGUCUCUGGGGCCCCACUCAGGGUUGGGUUGGAGAAGGCUGAAUGCUGCGUGGAAGGAGAUUUCCUAUGUUUCUGAUCUGGCUUGAGAGCUUUUUGAUGGCUGGGAGGGCCGGGUACUCUUUCUUAAGACAUUGAUAUAACAGCCCCAAAGAGCUGACUUGAUCAUCAGGGCCAGACCCCUCACCUCGGAGUAGAUGAGAAACUCCAGAUGAAGGGGAAUCUAUCUGAAUGACUCAUCUUUUCCUCCCCUGGGACUCCAGAAAGGAUCUGCACUAUUCCAUUUCAGUGGCAAGAUAUCUCCGUCCUCUUCUCUCUGCCAUUUCCAGAGAGCUCAUUUGAGACACACUAAUCAAAACCAACCGGGUCAUGUUACAGAGGGGAAAACUGAGGCCCAGAGAGAGGAAAUCCUGGCCACAGUCUGUUCCUUGAGUCUCCUUGUUGAGCUUACAGAGGGUCAACGCUGUGGGGUCAAUGCUUGUGUUACAAAAAAGUCACAUCCUACCUUCAUUUGAAAACCAUGUUGUUAUCCAUUCACAACCACCAGGCUGGCUAAUUUUAAAAAUGGAAAAUAAAUGUUGGUGAGAAUGUGGAGAGAUCAGAACCCUUGGGUGUUGUUGGUGGGAAUGUAAAAUGGUGCAUCUGCUGUAAAAAACAGUUUGGUGAUUUCUUAAAAACUUACACAUAAAGCUACCAUAUGACCCAGCAAUUCCACUCCUAGGUAUAUGCCCAAGAGAAAGGAAAAGCGAUGUCAACACGAAAACUUGCACGUGAAUGUCCAUAGCAAUGCUACUCUCUACUGCCAAGAGGUAGAAACAGAUGUCCAUCACUGAUGAAUGGAUAAAUAAAAUGUAGUCUAUUAAGGCAAUGGAAUAUUAUUCAGACAUAAAAAAAUGAGGAUCUACAGUGUGGGUGAACCUUGAAGAUAUUGUGCUAAGGGAAAGAAGGCAGACACAAAUGGGUAAACAUUGCAUGAUUCCAUUCAUAUGAAAUUUCCAGAAUUUGUCCAAGAAAAUCCAUAGUGGAAGACAGCUGAUGAGUGGUUUACAGGGACUUGGGAGAGGGAAGAAGGAAAGUGACUGGCGAAUAGGUAUGGGGUUUCCCUUUGGGGUGAUGGAAAUGUGUUGGAACUAAAUAGUGGUGAUGGCUGCAUAGCAUGUGAGUUUAAUGUACUAAAUGCCAUUGAAUUGUACACUUUAGAAUGGUUACUUUUAUGCUAGGUGAGUUUUACCUCAAUAAAAAUUAAAACCAGGCUGGUUGCUUACACCCGUAAUCCCAGCACCUUGGUUGGCUGAGGCAGGAGGAUCACUUGAGCCCAGGAGUUCAAGACCAGCCUGGGCAACAUAGGGAGACCUUGUCUCUAAAAAAAAAAAAAAAAAAAAAUUUGCCAGGCAUGGCAGGCGUACCUGUGGUCCCAGCUACUUGGGAGGCUGAGGUGGGAGGACCAGCUGGGCCCAGGGGGUUCAAGGCUGCAGUGAUUCUUGAUCGCACCUCUGCACUCCAGCCUGGGCAUCACAGCGAAACCCCAGCAACCCCAGUCUCUAAAUAGAUAAAUAAAACCAUGUUGUUUAUGUCUGAGGAACUUUUGAAUGCCAUUCUUACACUGUGUCGAUAGAGGAUGAUGUGAAGUCGCAGCGGAACACUUACCAGUGUAUGCCCGGUUCUGAGCCCUUACAGCUCCUCUAGUUCUCACGGCAGCCCUGUCACAAAGCUAUCCUCAUUAUUACCAUUUUACAGAGGGGGAAACUGAGGCCCUGAAUGAUAAAGCAGAUAGCCCCAUGUCAUCAAGGAAGGGUGGAGCUGGGAUUUGAAUCCAAGCAGUUUGGCUCCAGAGCCCAUGCGCUAAAGCGUCACAGUGAGACCCUGACUUCGAGUAAGAACCCACACCACUCUGAGCCCUGACACUGCAGUGUGGAUCAGAGGACUAGGGUGGCGGUGAGAAUGGAUACCUGGGCCUUAAAGCUGCUCCGCCAGGCCCAGAGCCACCCUUCCUCAAAAGUGCCUUGCUUGGGCUUGGUGGGCCUUGAAACAACAGUUUGAGGCUUCCUAUCCAUCCCCAGGGGUUCCCUGGGUAAUCAUGAUUAAUGCCAGAACUAGGAGCCGGGUGCACUCAGGGCCCUGCUCAGUGAUUGGCCCUGUGAUCACCCACCCCGGCCCCUUGUUACCGGCCCCUGCUCCAUAGUGGGCAGCCCGUGGAUUCCCUAAUGAAUUCUGUCAGCCCAGCGUGCAGGAGAUGGACAGAUAGAGAGGCCAAAUCCCAAAGUGGAUUUAUAAGUGGAAAUCCAGGGAUAAAUGCGGGGUUGGCGUAGGUGAGGGGAGUUGACCACAUCCACUGCUAAAUCUCAGAUUCCAAGAGGAGCUUAAUUCGUAAGGCUAUGUGCUAGAAAAGUCUGCAUUAGCCACUUUGGCGUGAGUAUAUCUCUAAAACCACUAAUGAAAUUGUGCUUUGGUCAAUCAACAUUUCUGGGGCCAGUGGCAUGGGUAAUCACUGGGCUUGCGUUGUGCUUUUAGACAGGGAAGCCAAUGUGGUCCCUGGUACACGCAGUUUUCUUCAACACCGAACGUUUGUUUUUCCAUCUUGUGGGUAGUGAGCCUUUCUUGAGCCAAAAUAUAUGUAGCUCACCCAUACAACUUUAUUUUGUAGAAAAGGGAGGAUAAAAGCUCCAUUGACCAAGCAUCCGUCUCCUGCCACAUUCUGCCUGAGGCAGGCCCAUGUGGAUUAUUGCUUGAAUCUGGGAAGUGGUUAUUCUUGCAGGUGGGAAACUGAGGCUUUGGGAGAUGGGGUACCAUGUGCAGGGUCACAGAGCAAGUUGGGGCAAAACAAAAAACCCGAUUCAGUGCUGUGAGCCUGAAAAGUGAGUUCUCUCUGCUUCACCAAUGGUUCCCAGCAAGUGCCGUGGACCCUCAGGGAGCUGGAGAGCUGAGACUGUCUCAGAAAGCCGGCUUUGGAGUGGAUGGGGUGUAGGGAGUGAGUGGCAGGAGCUAAGUACAGGGCAGGAUGGGGCCCAAAUGCCUUGCUCAGUGUCUGCAGUGUCCAUCAACCUGUUUCCCUCUCCUGGCCACCUGGGAGAGGACUCUGGAGUUUCUUGGAUUCUGGAGGUCAAACCAUCAGGCAUGCACUUCCAAUAAGGCCUUACACCUGCACAUCAGUUGAAACUCCAAAAGCUGCACAGAUCUUUGGAGGACACAUCCUGGCAUGGCCACUCACAAGCUGUGUGACUUUGGGGCAAGUUGCUCAGCUUUCUUCUCCUACAAACUUAAACCCUGAUCUCAGUCUAUUGUCAGCCUAGGAAUAGCUGCAAUAACAAAAUAAGGAAAAGAAAAGAAAUUACUAUUGGGAUGGAUGGAAAAGAAUACAUCUCAGCCAUGUACCAGCUGUGUGCCCUUAGUCAAGUUACUCAGCCUCUCUGCGCUCAGUUUCCUUACCUGUAAAAUGGGCAUAUUUUACCUACUUUGAAGGUAUUGCCUGUCAUUAAAUGAGAUGAUACAUUUAAUGGCAUUAAAUGAGUGCUCAUUAAAGCACUUAGCAAAGCUCCUUGCAUAUGAUGUUCAAAAAACUGGCUGUUUUAUUGACACCAUCAUCAUCAUCAGUAUCAUCACUGUAAUUACCAUCAUUGUCACUGCCAUGAUUUCCACUACCAUCACAGUUAGCAUCAGCAUUAUCAUUUUCAUUACCAUCCUUAUCAUUGUCAUCAUCAUCACCACCAUCACCAUCACAGCCACGAUCUUCACCAACAUUCCCAUCAUAACCAUCACCAUCACAGCCACGAUCAUCACCAACAUUACCAUCAUCACCAUUACCACCACCAUCAUCAUCAUAAUCAUUAGCAUCACCGUCGUCACCACCACUAUCAUUACCAACAUCACUACUGUAACUAUCACCAUCACCAUCAUCACCAUUACCAUCAUCAUCAUCAUAAUCAUUAGCAUCACCAUCAUCAUCACCACCACCAUUACCAACAUCACUAAUGUAGCUAUCACCAUCACCAUCAUCACCGUUACCACCGCCAUGAUCGUCACAAUCAUUACCAUUACUAUCAUCAUUAUCAUCAUCAUCAUUAUCACGAUAGUUACCAUCAUCAUUGCCAUGGUUUCCAUUAUCAUCACAAUUAGCAUUAGCAUUAUCAUUUUCAUUACCAUCCUUAUCAUUGUCAUUAUCAUCACCAUCAUCACCAUUGCCAACACCAUCAUCAUAAUCAUUAUCAUCACCAUCAUCAUCACCACCACCAUCAUCACCAACAUCAACAUCAUAACUGUAACCAUAACCGUCAUCGUCACAAUCAUCACCAUUACCACCACCAUUGUCAUCACCAUCAUUUCUAUUAUUGACAUCAUCGAUUGCCAUGAUCAUCAUGACAAUCAGCAUCAUCUUCAUCAUUAUCGAUUGUCAUGAUCAUGAUCAUCAUGACAUCAGCAUCAUCUUCAUCAUUAUCAUCCUUUUCGUCAUCACCACCACCAUCGUCACGACCACCGUUAUUACCAUCAGAUGGGCUGUUGGUGUUUCCAUGGGACAGAUCUGUCAUAGUAAGUCUGAGUGAUGGUUUAGGACUUGAAGCUGAUUUUUUCUGGCUUGUGGUAGUUAAAAAUACUAUCCUGACAUUCUCUCCACUGUUUAUUGUUUUAGAAAAUCUAUUAGAAAAUUGCUUUCUUCCCAGUAUGGUUCUCAAUUAGCCAGCAUCAGGAUUUUCCACUGGCAUCUCGGAAUGUUCUCAUCAGAAACCUCCCGAAAGGCAUGAUCGUUGAAGCUGGGAGAUUUGCCCAAAGGCUGUCUGGGCACAGAGUUUCUAAUGCCAAUAUUAUUUGCUCAUGCCCAGCUCUUUCCAGCAAACAGAGGCCUUUCAAACUAUUAAUAUAUAAACCAACAGCACAAGCACUUUGAAAGGAGAAGAGUGUGGGGGCAGGGUGCAUUCAUCUAUCCGAGCUGCCAUGACAAAAUACCAAGGACUAGGUGGCUUAAACAACAGAAAUCUAUUAUCUCACCGUUCUGGAGGUUGGAAAGUUUGAGAUCAGGUGGCAGCAAAUUUGGUUUCUGGUGAGGGCUCUCUUCCUGGCUUAUAGAUGGCUGUCAUCUCACUGUGUCCUUUCCUCUGUGCUUUCGUAGUGUUGUGGGGGGUGGGACAGUGGGCAGGGCGGGGGGAGAGAAAGGGAGAGAGAGAGAAACCUGGUGUCUCUCUUCUCAUAAGGACACCAGUUCUAUCGGAUUAAGGUCCCACCCUUGUGACCUCACCUAUCAUUUAUUAUCUCCAUAAAGGCCCCAUCUCCAAGUAUAGUCUCAUUAGGGUUGAGGAUUCAAUAUGUGAAUUGGCCGGGGGACACAAAAAAGUCCAUAAGAGGAGGAAAGGGCAUAUUAAUGAAGCAUGUGCCAUGUGCCAGGCAUUGAACCAGGCACUUUCGUAGAUACCAUUUCAUUUGAGUCUCAAGAGGACUCCGUGAGGCAGGCAGCAUAAUCUCCAUUUUAUGAAUGAGGAAGCUGAGACCUAGUGAGUGUAAGCAAAUUGUUCAAUACCACACAGCUAGUAGGACCUGGGUUUUUAGUUCAGGUCUAUCUGACUUCAAAUACCACACCCUUUUUUAAUAUCAAUUAUUCUCAGCAAAUGGCCCAUGGACCCCUGGACAUUCUCUGAGGUCUAUGAGGUAAAAUCUUGUGUUGAUAGUAAUAUUAAUAUUGUAUCGUAAUGUUAGUAUUAAUACUAAUACUACUAACACUAAGUUAUAUUUUACUCUGUUGACUAAUCACUGAUGAUACAAAUCCAACAGUGGGGAAAACCGCUAAGGCUUAACUCGAAUCAAAAUGCUGGCCCCAAACUAUGCUAUGCCAUGCCAUGCCAUGCCAUGCCAUGCCACGCCACGCCAUGCCAUGCCAUGCCAUGCCAUGCUAUGCUAUGCUAUGCUAUGCUAUGCUAUGCUAUGCUAUGCUAUGCUAUGCUAUGCUAUACUAUGCUAAUAGUUACGGUAUUGUUCACCAUCAUGCAGUCAGUAAAACAUAAACACAUAAUCUUCAAUGAAGCAAUAAAAUUCGUUAAGGAUUGUCAAAUCUCAA